GUUAGUCUCCGGCGAGUUGUUGCCUGGGCUGGACGUGGUUUUGUCUGCUGCGCCCGCUCUUCGCGCUCUCGUUUCAUUUUCUGCAGCGCGCCAGCAGGAUGGCCCACAAGCAGAUCUACUACUCGGACAAGUACUUCGACGAACACUACGAGUACCGGCAUGUUAUGUUACCCAGAGAACUUUCCAAACAAGUACCUAAAACUCAUCUGAUGUCUGAAGAGGAGUGGAGGAGACUUGGUGUCCAACAGAGUCUAGGCUGGGUUCAUUACAUGAUUCAUGAGCCAGAACCACAUAUUCUUCUCUUUAGACGACCUCUUCCAAAAGAUCAACAAAAAUGAAGUUUAUCUGGGGAUCGUCAAAUCUUUUUCAAAUUUAAUGUAUAUGUGUAUAUAAGGUAGUAUUCAGUGAAUACUUGAGAAAUGUACAAAUCUUUCAUCCAUACCUGUGCAUGAGCUGUAUUCUUCACAGCAACAGAGCUCAGUUAAAUGCAACUGCAAGUAGGUUACUGUAAGAUGUUUAAGAUAAAAGUUCUUCCAGUCAGUUUUUCUCUUAAGUGCCUGUUUGAGUUUACUGAAACAGUUUACUUUUGUUCAAUAAAGUUUGUAUGUUGCAUUUA